CUGUCUUUCAUAGAAAUCAUUUGCCUUGUCCUGUCCCUCCCAAAUAAUAGUGUGUGAUUCAGAAAGCUGAUUAUGCUACCAAUAGUAAUAAUCACAAUGACAAUCACAACUGCUAUUUCUGAGUACACAUUGUGCCUUCAGUUAGCAAAAAUGUUAUCUUGACUUCUCACAUGAAUCCUGCAAGUUAGGUGUUAUCCCCAUUCCACACAUUAGGGAUAGAGACUAGGAGAGGUUCAGUUAUUUGUCCAAGUACCUAUAUCUAGUAAGUGCAGGAAUUGGGAUUUGAUGAUGGUUUGGUCUGCUCCAGAGCCUGUGCCCUUUAUAUAUCUCUGCAGAAAAAGCUGAGACAUUAAAACAAGGUAGAAGAAGGGAGGAGGGACAAAGGAAAGGAAAUAAAGAAGAUGGUGCUACCUUUUCUAAUGCAUUAGCCUUAAAGGCUGAUAGAGGUAAAGGUGGCAGAAGAGGAUCCAAAUAAAGGGAGUGGACAUCAGGCCCACUGAGCGUCCUUCAGAGAAGAGAUGCAAAGAUUUUUGCCUGGAAAGGUUGCCCCAGGGCUUUUUGGUGGGUAGCCUUCAUGCUACUUCCCUUGGACUGACUCACUCAAGGUUUUACGAAAUAGGUGUUCAGCAGCAGAAAGGGUCUAAUUUAAAGACGAAUGAGGGAUUAAGAAAAGAGUUAGACCUAGGCUAAUUUCCCCAAGGAAGCCAAAGCUUAAUUUACUUGUUUAACUUUCAUUCUUUUAACACCAUUUAUGUACCAGGUUCUGGGAUGUGUGCUAGUUAGAGAGAUUUUAAAAACUUGUCUUCAGGGAGCCUAAGAGCCUGCUGGGAAGUACACUAAAGUCUUUGGCAUGUGGGAAUUUAACAAAAUUUUAACUAUUCUUUAGCCACCAGAAGUAAAGUCUAGAUUUGUGGUUCCCAACCUCAAAUGCACAUUGGAAUCACCUGGGGAACUUUUUAAAAGCUAAAUUCCGUGACUUCACAGCUAGAGAUUCUGAGUUAAUCUAGGGUGCUGUCUGGAUGUUGGGACUUUUUCAAAACAAUGUGGGUGGGGCUCCUUAGAGAAGUGAUUGAUUCCAGGGCUGGGCAGGGAAAAAACAAGAUGAGACAAGAGCAUUUUGUGAUGAAGUGGCCAUUCUGCCUGCCCCUCAGAACCUCUCUGUACUCUCAACCAACAUGAAGCAUCUCUUGAUGUGGAGCCCAGUGAUCGCGCCUGGAGAAACAGUGUACUAUUCUGUCGAAUACCAGGGGGAGUACGAGAGCCUGUACACGAGCCACAUCUGGAUCCCCAGCAGCUGGUGCUCACUCACUGAAGGUCCUGAGUGUGAUGUCACUGAUGACAUCACGGCCACUGUGCCAUACAACCUUCGUGUCAGGGCCACAUUGGGCUCACAGACCUCAGCCUGGAGCAUCCUGAAGCAUCCCUUUAAUAGAAACUCAACCAUCCUUACCCGACCUGGGAUGGAGAUCACCAAAGAUGGCUUCCACCUGGUUAUUGAGCUGGAGGACCUGGGGCCCCAGUUUGAGUUCCUUGUGGCCUACUGGAGGAGGGAGCCUGGUGCCGAGGAACAUGUCAAAAUGGUGAGGAGUGGGGGUAUUCCAGUGCACCUAGAAACCAUGGAGCCAGGGGCUGCAUACUGUGUGAAGGCCCAGACAUUCGUGAAGGCCAUUGGGAGGUACAGCGCCUUCAGCCAGACAGAAUGUGUGGAGGUGCAAGGAGAGGCCAUUCCCCUGGUACUGGCCCUGUUUGCCUUUGUUGGCUUCAUGCUGAUCCUUGUGGUCGUGCCACUGUUCGUCUGGAAAAUGGGCCGGCUGCUCCAGUACUCCUGUUGCCCCGUGGUGGUCCUCCCAGACACCUUGAAAAUAACCAAUUCACCCCAGAAGUUAAUCAGCUGCAGAAGGGAGGAGGUGGAUGCCUGUGCCACGGCUGUGAUGUCUCCUGAGGAACUCCUCAGGGCCUGGAUCUCAUAGGUUUGCGGAAGGGCCCAGGUGAAGCCGAGAACCUGGUCUGCAUGACAUGGAAACCAUGAGGGGACAAGUUGUGUUUCUGUUUUCCGCCACGGACAAGGGAUGAGAGAAGUAGGAAGAGCCUGUUGUCUACAAGUCUAGAAGCAACCAUCAGAGGCAGGGUGGUUUGUCUAACAGAACACUGACUGAGGCUUAGGGGAUGUGACCUCUAGACUGGGGGCUGCCACUUGCUGGCUGAGCAACCCUGGGAAAAGUGACUUCAUCCCUUCGGUCCUAAGUUUUCUCAUCUGUAAUGGGGGAAUUACCUACACACCUGCUAAACACACACACACAGAGUCUCUCUCUAUAUAUACACACGUACACAUAAAUACACCCAGCACUUGCAAGGCUAGAGGGAAACUGGUGACACUCUACAGUCUGACUGAUUCAGUGUUUCUGGAGAGCAGGACAUAAAUGUAUGAUGAGAAUGAUCAAGGACUCUACACACUGGGUGGCUUGGAGAGCCCACUUUCCCAGAAUAAUCCUUGAGAGAAAAGGAAUCAUGGGAGCAAUGGUGUUGAGUUCACUUCAAGCCCAAUGCCGGUGCAGAGGGGAAUGGCUUAGCGAGCUCUACAGUAGGUGACCUGGAGGAAGGUCACAGCCACACUGAAAAUGGGAUGUGCAUGAACACGGAGGAUCCAUGAACUACUGUAAAGUGUUGACAGUGUGUGCACACUGCAGACAGCAGGUGAAAUGUAUGUGUGCAAUGCGACGAGAAUGCAGAAGUCAGUAACAUGUGCAUGUUUGUUGUGCUCCUUUUUUCUGUUGGUAAAGUACAGAAUUCAGCAAAUAAAAAGGGCCACCCUGGCCAAAAGCGGUCUUUAAA